UGACAUUCUUCUGGACAAUGAGUCCCAUCAUCUCUCCACCAUGCACCUUGUGACUCCCUCCUCUGCUGACAACAGAUAACCACCUUUAACUGUAACUUUCCACAGCCUACCCCAGCCCUAUAAAGCUGCCCCUCUCCUAUCUCCCUUCGCUGACUCUCUUUUCAGACUCAGCCCACUUGCACCCAAGUGAAUUAACAGCCUUGUUGCUCACACAAAGCCUGUUUAGGUGGUCUUCUAUACGGACAUGCUUGACACUUGGUGCCAAAAUCUGGGCCAGGGGGACUCCUUCGUGAGACCGGCCCCCUGUCCUGGCCCUCAUUCCGUGAAGAGAUCCACCUGCGACCUCGGGUCCUCAGACCAGCCCAAGGAACAUCUCACCAAUUUCAAAUCGGAUCUCCUCGGCUUAGUGGCUGAAGACUGAUGCUGCCCGAUCGCCUCAGAAGCCCCUUGGACCAUCACAGAUGCCGAGCUUCGGGUAACUCUUACGGUGGAGGGAUCUGCAAUCAGAACUAUUGAACUUCUCCAUUCAGACCGCCACUCACACCUAUGGGAAAAGGGUAAUGUAUCAUCGGCUUAGCAACAGGGAAUACUAUUCGUAUGAUGGAAAAUGGGGACAAAAGGCUUUGGUACAUAAAACAUUAUUCCUUCCUUGGCCUAAAAACUCAUCGCCACCUACAUUAAAGCUAAUAUGCCUGAUUACUGUUUUUAGAGAACUUAUUUUAUUAGGGCAGUUCCAAGCUCAAAAAUACGCUAACUGGCACCUUGUUAGCUACAUAAAAAUGCACCCUAGACCCGAAACUUACUAGACUCAUUAUAAAAUUUUCUUUAAGGUGUCCACGCAGUCCCUGGUCACACUUGAAGCAGUCCGGAGAAAUAUCAGCCCUACCCCAGUAAUCCCCAGAAGGAACUUACACUUUUUUUUAAUCUUUUCCUACAACUUCAUAUUUUAUAAAUAAAAAGACAAAAAUGUCAGGCCUGUGAGCUGAAGCUUAGCCAUUGUAACCCCUGUGACCUGCACAUAUCCGUCCAGGUGGCCUGCAGGAGCCAAGAAGUCUGGAGCAGCCGAAAAACCACAAAGAAGUGAAACAGCCAGUUCCUGCCUUAACUAAUUAACCCACCUUACGACAUUCCACCAUUAUGACUUGUCCACCAUUAUGACUUGUUCCUGCCCUGCCCCAACUGAUCAAUCAACCCUGUGACAUUCUUCUCCUGGACAAUGAGUCCCAUCAUCUCUCCACCAUGCACCUUGUGACCCCCUCCUCUGCUGAGGAUAACCACCUUUAACUGUAACUUUCCACGCCUACCCAAGCCCUAUAAAGCUGCCCCUCUCCUAUCUCCCUUCACUGACUCUCUUUUCGGACUCAGCCCACUUGCACCCAAGUGAAUUAACAGCCUUGUUGCUCACACAAAGCCUGAUUGGGUGUCUUCUAUACGGACACGCGUGACAGGAACCUCAACCCAAAGGCAGUCUGAUGAGGUGUCUAAGAUAAAAGUAGCGGCACAAAGGCUUUUGUAAACAGAGGCGUUUCAUGUGGUUUUCCUUUCCUUUCCUUAUAUGUGAAAAGGUGACAGAAAAGAAAUCUUCCUAAAAGAGUCAGCCACUGCUCUGUGGAACGAUGAUCAUUUAAAUGCCACGUCGAUUUGAAACGUACAACAAAGGGACUAACAGUUGAGAACCAUGUGGAUUGCAGUGGAGACGCUGGCGUUAGAGAAUGCGGGGAGGGAAACGUUCAUUACAAGAUUUACGGCCAGCCCAAGGGGGAGCGAGGCUGGGGGACCGGGUCGCGGAGACCCGGCUUCGCACACCUUUUGGAAGACUCAGGGAGAAGCGGGGGCCGCCUUCGGGGGGAAAGGCGGGACUGGGGAGCCCACAGGCCAUGGCUCCUCCCACAGGAUCCCCAGGCCGGAGGCGGGAUCCCCCCAUGAUCCUCCCGUGGCCCCCGCACAAUCUGGGGAGAUGCGGAGCUGCCCAGAGAGGGCUCUGGGGCGACAGUCACUGCGCAGGGACAGGACAGGACUCCCGGAGUCCCAGCUGCCGGCCCAGCCCCACCCUGCGGCCGAGAGGACCGAGGGCCGAGCUGCUCCAGGGGAACUCGGGUCCCAGACCCCGGAGUCGCAGCGGACAGGCCCGGGUCCCGCCACAGCCAGAUCCGGCUGGUUCCACCAGCUCCUCCUCCGGUCUCGGGACGUCCGGCCCCGCACACUCAGCAUUUCCGGCUUCCGGGUGUCCCGGCGUCCUCCCCUGGGCCUGCUCACGUCGCAGAGGGGCGGCGACGGGGAUUAGAGGGGAGGAGGGCCUGCGCGAGCAGCAAAGACCCCAAACCCCAAAAAACAAAGAAACCGCCAGAAACUGAAGCUUCCACAGCCCGCCACGUCCCCCGGCUACGGCUACGCUCCUGAUUGGAUAGUUAGUACGGCCCCUAGUGCCCCUGAUUGGAUACCGCUUCAGGUCCCGCCCCCUGGGGUUAGAAAGACAGGAGACCCGAGAAGACACUUGGCUGCGUGGAGCCCAAAUGGGCGGUUCCUGGCAACUGGGCUUGUUGUCUUCCUCGUGUCAGGAUGUAAAAAGAAAAGUAGAGGUUCUUCUUCAAAGACUUCCUUCUUCAUCUAAUUAAGAAUAAAUAGUGUUUGAAAUGCUUGGUUUUUGGUGCCAUAAA